ACUCCCGCCUCCAUGUUCCCGGAGUCGCCUGGAAGCGUCCGCCCAAGGUCGCGGGCCGCUUGGGGAGUCAGCAGCGCGCCAGGCCCCUUCGGGCCCCACACGCAUUAGGUGCCUUCUUGAUGGGUACGGAGUGAACGCGGGCGGCGGCGGGACCGAGGCAGCGCCCAGUUUGUAACCGCCGCGCCGCCCGUGCCCGCGCGCGCCACACCCCAGCGCGCUUCCGGCCGGGCCACGUGACCGCGCGUGCACGUGUUCCGGCCUCUCCGCUUCGCCGCUCCGAACCUCCUCCUGGUCGUCCCGGCAUUCGUCCACGCGGAGCCGGCUUGGGCGGGGCCCGGGAGGCGGCGGCCGGAGAAGCCGCGGAGACGCGAGCGCCGAGCGUCGCGAGGGAGCAGGCCCGGGCAGGCAAGCGGCGGCCUCCGCCAUGAACCCCAGGGGCCUGUUCCAGGACUUCAACCCCAGUAAGUUUCUCAUCUACACCUGCCUGCUGCUCUUCUCGGUGCUGCUGCCCCUCCGCCUGGACGGCAUCAUCCAAUGGAGCUACUGGGCCGUCUUUGCCCCCAUAUGGCUGUGGAAGCUUCUAGUCGUCGCAGGCGCCUCCGUGGGCGCGGGCGUUUGGGCCCGCAACCCUCGCUACCGCACCGAGGGAGAGGCCUGUGUGGAGUUCAAAGCCAUGCUGAUCGCUGUGGGCAUCCACCUGCUGCUGCUCAUGUUCGAAGUCCUGGUCUGCGACAGGGUGGAGAGGGGCACCCACUUCUGGCUGCUGGUCUUCAUGCCUCUCUUCUUCGUGUCCCCCGUGUCCGUGGCUGCCUGCGUCUGGGGCUUUCGACACGAUAGGUCGCUGGAGCUGGAGAUCCUGUGCUCGGUCAACAUCCUGCAGUUCAUCUUCAUCGCCCUAAAGCUGGACAGGAUUAUUCACUGGCCGUGGCUGGUGGUGUUUGUGCCCCUGUGGAUCCUCAUGUCGUUCCUUUGCCUGGUCGUCCUCUAUUACAUCGUCUGGUCCCUCCUGUUCCUGCGGUCCCUGGAUGUGGUUGCCGAGCAGCGGAGAACACACGUGACCAUGGCUAUCAGUUGGAUAACGAUUGUCGUGCCUCUGCUCACUUUUGAGGUCCUGCUGGUUCACAGAUUGGAUGGCCACAAUACAUUCUCCUACGUCUCCAUAUUUGUCCCCCUUUGGCUUUCCUUACUAACUUUAAUGGCCACAACAUUUAGGCGAAAGGGGGGCAAUCAUUGGUGGUUUGGCAUUCGCAGAGACUUCUGUCAGUUUCUGCUUGAAAUUUUCCCAUUUUUAAGAGAAUAUGGGAACAUUUCAUAUGAUCUCCAUCACGAAGAUAGUGAAGAUGCUGAAGAAACAUCAGUUCCAGAAGCUCCGAAAAUUGCUCCAAUAUUUGGAAAGAAGGCCAGAGUAGUUAUAACCCAGAGCCCUGGGAAAUACGUUCCCCCCCCUCCCAAGUUAAAUAUUGAUAUGCCAGAUUAAACUCCUAGAGAGGACCCAGGCACACACAGACUCCACUUGGCCUUCGCCUCUUGUUCAUUCAUCCCAAACCUGGAAAUGGAAACAGGCUUCAAACACUCGUCUCACGCCGUGUUUGAGAUCACCGCCUCAUCAGUAUGCAUCAUAGAUGGAGGUGGUUUCAGUAUGUGGGUGUGUGUGAUGUGUACCUGGGUAAGAGACUUGCUUUCCAGGUUCGCACUUUCAGGUGUAGCUGGGGGCAGUAAGUCGAAUUGUUUUAGUAGGUCCUCAAAAGGAAUAACCACACAGCUGUUUGUUUAAAUGCUACUGUACCUAUCAAAACUAUUGUUUAAAAAGUAUUUUUAUACACUGCUAAUCUAAAAUUGUAUUUCAGAUUGUGCCUGUCAUAACAAUAGCAAAUGUAAAAAGUUCUCUUUCCCACCACUUGUUUAUAAACCUCAUAGUUGAUAUUUUUAGUGUUCCUACUGUUAAAAUACUCUCUCCUUGGGCUUUGCUGAUACUGGUCUUUAAUAUUCUGAUAGGUGAAUUUUUCUAAUGGAAUGAACCCAUGCAUAUAUAGUAUUUAUAUGAAUAUUUUAGCAGUGUAAUAUGUUGAAUUCUAGUUCUCUGCAUUACCAUUAUUACGUUAAAGUAUUUUUUAAAGCUUAGGUGUGAAGAUAUGUGUCUAUUGCAGAUGUCCUUGAAAACUGCAUAAAACAGUAUGUGCCUGGUGUGGAUCUUACCAAAGUACUAGGCAUGAAUGUAGGGACUGCAAAUCCCAUGGGUCUUAAUAUUUAGGUGUUAGUAACCAAGGUCUCUGGUAGUACCCGUUAGUAGAGGAAGAGGCCACUGCCCUUGGGAACUUGUGACAGGCUCUAGUGUGGUACCAGGCCAUAAAGUGACACUGUUAUUUAGCAACUUGAAUUUUUCCACACAGGUAGUAACUGUGUGGAAAUAAGCAACAAGUGGUUUGUCCAUUUCUAAGAAUCUUAAACUAUUAGUUGGCUGUAGUGUGAAGCAUUACUUGUCAUUGGAAAGAUGGAGAGAGUGGCCUUAACCGGAAGUGGUCAGUAGAAGCAGGUGUCAUUUUAAGGGCCAAACUUUAAUCUGUCAGCAAUAGGGAAACAACUGUUCAAAUUAUCUUUGUAGAUAAGAACAGUGUUUCUUUUUUCUUUUCUUUUGUUUUUUUGUUUGUUUGUUUUGUUUUGUUUUGAGACAGAGUUUCACUCUUGUUGCCCAGGCUGGAGUGCAAUGGCACAAUCUUGAUCUCAGCUCGCCGCAGCCUCCGCCUCCCGGUUCAAGCGAUUCUUCUGCCUCAGCCUCGCGAGUAGCUGGGAUUACAGGCAUGCACCACCACGCCUGGCUAAUUUCGUAUUUUUAAUAGAGACAGGGUUUCUCCAUGUUGGUCAGGCUGGUCUCAAACUCCUGACUUGAGGUGAUCUGCCCGCCUUGGCCUCCCAAAGUGCUGGGAUUACAGGCGGGAACCACUGCACCCGGCAGGUACAGUGUUUCUUUAGGUGCUGGUGGUACACCAGGGAAUCAGGGCAGAAGCUGGAUCCUGCAAGAGUAAUGUUUGAGAACAAAUAAAUACUUUCGAAAGGAGGUCGAAACAAAAAGGAGUGUAGGUGUUAUUACUGCAGAGAAGACUGAAUGGAGUCCACUUUUCUUAUUAGUAACUUACUAAAAAUGAUCUCAAAUGGGCUCCACACACUUUGCCCUGGCCAUGAGGCAAACUUGUUGGGUUUGGAGAAAAACACAUAACCCUAAAUUCACUAUUUUUGCCCUAUAUAAAACAUUAAAAUAACAUGCUCUGUACACAUGCUGUCAACAAAAGCCAGCUCUAGGAACCUGAGUGCCAGAAUGCCUGAGGGAGCUACAGCUGGGCUUAGUUGGCUGGGAUUGAGCUCGCUGUCUGAGGGAGCUCGCUCUGUCUCUCUCACACUGGCAGUUUACACCAGCCGGCAGCCCUGAGCAGCAGUGGGUGUAACUUUUUAUAAAUAAGGAUUCAUUGAUUCAUUCAUAUUCUCAAUAUUUCUUGAAGACCUACCCCGAGCCAAGCAUGGUGCCAGGCAGUGGGGAUGCAGUGGAGAGCAAACAGCCCUGCCCAUGCAAAGUGUCCUGUACGGUGAGAAGUGUGAGCUGCACCCACAAAGGGAAAGAGCCCAGUGCAGCUUUUGCAAAAUGCAGGGAAGGAUGCUGCUAGCCUCAGGGUGACCUAGAACUUUAAGCUCAUCUUUGUUUUCAGGAGCCCAGUGCCUCCCCUCCACCCCUAAAGAAUAUCUCAAAGACGUGGAUUUUCAUUUCAGUAAGAUUUAGGGGUGCAUGGGCAGGCAGUGCUGGAGGAACUGGGAGGCAGGUUUGGAGGCUGCAGUGGGACCACUGGCCCCUCCUGGCUACAGUUUCAGGCCAGGAGCUUGUUGGCACCUGGUGCAAACUCCCAAACCUGAGGGGUCCCCACAACCCCCCAGCCCAUCUUAACUUCCUCUUCCCCCAAGCUAUCUGGUGUUGGAAAGCCAGCAUCUAGUGUGGAAACAAGCUUUCUCACCAGGUAGGCCAUCCGCUGUCAGGACCAUUAGGUAAAAACAGAAGUGACAGGUUGUAGGAAGUCGUUCGAUCUGUGAGGCUGCGAGCACUUCAGUGCCUGGGAUUUACCUAACUGCCAUGAAACACUGAUUAUCCAGCAUUCAGCAUGUGUCAGAUUCUGUAACUAUUUCUCCUGUGAUGUAUCAGUCAGCUUUUGCUGCAAAACAGCAUCAGAAAUCUCAGUGGUCUACAACUAGAUUCCCAUUCUUGGGUAGUCUACAAGUUGGCUUCUAGGUUAUGCUCCAGGCUGGGGGUCUGAUCACGUCUGCUCCACAACAUGUCCCGUAUUCUGGGUCCCUGGUUGAAGCAGCAGCUUACCUUGGGCCGUGUUCUUUCUCAUGGCAGAAGCACAGGAGGCCAAGCCCUACCUUGCAAGCACAAAUACAGCCCCUGCUCACUUUCUGUUGGCCACAACACAUGGCCAUGCCUGACCUCUGUGGGGUGAGGCAGUGCAUGGCCAAGGAACAAGCACAGUCCACACAGGGGGCUGUCACUCCGUGACCUCAGUAUUACAAAAUGGUUCUCAAGGAGUCGCAAAAUGUGUGGCAGAUCAUCCAUGAUUUGUUUCCCGUGUGCUUUACGAAUAUCCUGAAAUUUUUAAAAGCUGUUUCCAUUAGAAGGGAUCUGUUGGGGAUUUGAGGUGAGAUGAGAAAGACCCUGCAUUCCAGCCCCUCAGUUAGCAGUGGUGAGGCCGGAGUACUCCACACGGGACAGUUUUAGGAAAGUGCUGGAAUCCAAAGUUUCUCCGGAGGGCUAUGCAAGGCGCUUUGGAAAGGCGAAGCCUGGGCGCAGGGAGCCCAGCCAUGUAGGUAGAAGCAGCAGACGGUGAGGGAGGCCAUCCCCACCUGGCCCUGCCAGGGCCCUGACUCAGUGAAGGAAGCUGUUGGGAUACAGGUCAUUCAGCCGGGCAGGAAAGAUGGGAUGAAGCCCAGCAAGUUCACAGGGAUCCGGGAAGUUGUGUGGCUGGAAACCCAGGCAGGGCUGCACCACAGGGACCAUUUGCUGGAGAUGCAGCACUUGCCACAGCCACCACCACUGACAGCAUGACACCCACAAAAAGGGAGCCUCCAGCUGCACCCCUGCUGCUGCGAGUACUUCCUCAGCUGUCUGCCAUGAGCUUAAGGUUAAGUACCAGGAGGGAGGAUAUGAUUGGGCAAACCUCAGGCAUGUGUUCAUUCUGUAGCUUCCAGAACAUGCGAGGAGAGAGCAUCUGGCUCCUUUGUCUCGAGGAGGAGGGGGCAGGACUCUGCCAGAACUCACUCGAUAAAAGAUUUUCCCAAAAGGAAGGGUGUUCAGAUGACAAAAGUCCACUACACCACUUUCCUUGGCUAUCUGAUGCACCCCCAUCUUCCCAUGCGCGCACCUCAGAAAUCAGGCUCCCACCUGACAUAACACAACCAUGCCUCACAAAAAGACAGUGGUUUAUCCCUUCCCUAGGAGAAAAGAGAGGCAAUGCCAAGCUGCUUCAUCAACUGUUAAUACUUCUUCCAGCCCGCAACCCAGGAUAUCUGCAGGUGUCUCUCCCUCUGGUUUGGUCAUGGCUCUCUCUGUUCUAGAAUGUAUGGGUUAAAGUCGGCUGCCACACCAUGCCCUCGGCAGUGUGGUCCAAGGACCCCUGAGGGUCCUCAAGGUCCUUCCUUUCCCAACCCCACGUGGUUUUCUUCAGUCAGGAUACCAUACUGCAACAGACCGAAGGCGGAAGCAGCUAUGAGGAUGCAGCAGCCUUCUGUUAAGCCAGGCUUUAAGGAUCUGCAAAAAUGUAAAACGAUGCCACUCCUACUGAUGAAAUAUAUUGUUUUGGAAAAUAUAGGUUUAAAAAUUUUUUUAAGGUAACAUGUAAUGGAUGUAUAGUCUUCAAAUGGAUGAAUAAAUGUUUUUCAGAGUUA